GAGUCACAGAUGCUGGGAAGUAUGGCCCGAAAGAAACCUCGAAAUACCUCAAGGUUGCCCCUGGCUUUAAACCCCCUGAAGAGCAAGGACGUGUUGGCAGUGCUGGCUGAGAGGAACGAGGCUAUAGUACCAGUUGGGGCAUGGGUGGAACCUGCCUCACCAGGUAGUUCGGAAAUCCCAGCAUAUGUGAGUGUCAGUUUGAUCCAAAUAUGGUGGGGUUCCCCACCACCCUUUUUAUUAGCCUUCUCUAAUCCUGGGUGCUUAAAGAUGAACAGUCCGAGGAUGCUGUUUCUAUUCUGCCAUAAAUAGUUUAUGCUCUUGCAUUAGGAUUAUAGAACAAGUAUUUGCCAAAACUUGACUGCAGCUUUAGUUGGCAUAAUCAAAUAUUUAUUACUCACCUACUAUAAUAUAUAGAGCAUAAUCUACAUGGAACAGGUUAUAUAGAUAUAUAUCUGUAUAUCAGUUUACUUCAGACUCUUGAUUGCUUGUUAUGCCCAAGACAUAAGCACUAUCUACAUCUUCCAGACACUGCAACUUAGUAUGGAUGAUAGUUGGCAUACUUCAAGUAACAUUAAUUGGUUGCUUAAGGUUUAUGAUAAAUUUUGUAAUGAGGAUUCAGGCAAAAUGGAGUAAUAGAAUAAAGGAGAAAGAGAUGAACUCUGAUAAUCUGAGAAAGUCUAACUAGAAAUUCCAUGGUUUCUGAUAGUCUUUCACCAAACUGUGCCCCUUAGCUAUUUGUUCAAAUUUAACUUGGCACUUACCACAUUGUGUUAUAGUAGAUUGUUUAUAUAUCUUUUCCUGAUGCAGUGUGAGCUCCUUGAGCGUAGAGAACAAAUGUCAUUUAUCAUCACAUUCCCACUUUUAUCUUAAAUACUGCCUAAUCAAUAUAGACACUCAUGAAGUAUUUAUGAAAGGCACAAAAUGUCUUCUGUAUGUGUAGACAAGGUGCUGAACAUGGAUGAAAAAAGGAUGAGAUAUGUUCCCUCAGUGUACUUGAUCUCAGAAGAGAAAUGAGAUGUGUUUAAAUGUUAAAGUAAUGCAAUAUACUAUAUUCAUUUUAUUUAUGUUUGCACAUAUGUAUGUAUAUUCAUUGAUUUAUUCCUACCCUGCCUAUUUCCAAAAAGGAUUUUAAGAGUCUAGGUGGUAUCUCUAUCUAAGUUCUAAGAAUAUAAUGCUCAAUCAAGAAGCUAUGACGUUGGGUUGAUGUGACCCAGGAAAGUGUAAUGAAGAAUUUGAUCGGAGAAGGGAAGGGAAUGAUUCUCCUAUUAAGGAGAAUGAGGAGAGUAAGAAGUAAGCAAGGUUCAGGAUUCUAAGGGUAGAUUAGAUCGAUUGGAGUGGAAAGCUUAGUAGGAGAAUGGUUGCUGACAGGAUUAUGGAAAAUAGGGAUGGUAGAGUACCUUAGGAAAUUUUGGAGAAGGGAUUGACUUUGUUUAAUAUUUACAGGUGAAUGUCAUGAUCAACCAGUGUUUUCUUUAGAUGAAUUGCUUCAAAGGUUUUGAAGGAUAGGGAGUGAUUGGAUCCUGGGGAUAAAUUAGAAUAUAAUUAUAAUAAUUUAAGCAUGGAGUAUAGCAUCGAAACUUUGUUAGUGGUAAGAAAUAGAGAAGAACAGCCUUGAAAAAGGAUGAUUGAAGUGCUUGAGCCCACGAAUUGUAGGCUGCAGUGAACUAUGAUCAUACUACUGCACUCUAGCCUGGGCAAUAGAGUGAGACCCCAUCUCUGGAAAAAAAAAAGGAGUGGAAUGAGAAGGGAUGAAUGCAGGAAACACCCCACAAGACUUGACAUCAGCAUAUUUAAUUGAAGAAGAACUAAAGGAACAGCUAAGAAAAAAACAAGAAGCUUUGAAACAUUUUCAGAAACAAGUUAAAUACCGAGUAAAUCAACAAAUUAGGUUGAGAAAAAAGCAACAGCUUCAGAAGUCUUAUGAAAGAGCACAAAAAGAAGGCUCCAUAGCCAUGCAGUCUUCAGCAACACACUUAACUUCCAAAAGGACAAGUGUUUUUCCAAACAAUUUGAAUGUUGCUAUUGGAAGUUCUAGGUUACCUCCUUCCCUGAUGCCUGGGGAUGGAAUAGAGGAUGAAGAGAAUCAGAACGAAUUAUUCCAACAACAAGCCCAGGCUCUUAGUGAAACUAUGAAACAGGCACGUCACCGGCUAGCAUCCUUUAAAACCGUGAUUAAAAAAAAGGGAUCAGUGUUUCCAGAUGAUGGAAGGAAAAGCUUUCUUACCAGAGAGGAAGUGCUUUCCAGGAAACCAGCAUCCACUGGGAUAAAUACAGGAAUAAGAGGAGAGUUGCCCAUUAAGGUCCAUCAAGGUCUUUUAGCUGCUGUACCUUACCAGAAUUAUAUGGAAAAUCAGGAACUUGACUAUGAGGAACCUGACUAUGAGGAAUCUUCAUCUCUUGUAACUGAUGAGAAAGGGAAAGAAGAUUUGUUUGGGAGAGGCCAGCAGGACCAGCAGGCUAUCCAUUCUGAAGAUAAGAACAAACCUUUCAGCAGAGUUCAGAAAGUAAAAUUCAAAAAUCCAUUAUUUGUUCUGAUGGAAGAGGAAGAACAAAAGCAGUUACAUUUUGAGGGCCUUCAGGAUAUUCUGCCAGAAGCCCAGGAUUAUUUUCUAGAAGCCCAAGGUGAUUUGCUGGAAACCCAGGGUGAUUUGACAGGAAUCCAGAGUGUUAAGCCAGAUACCCAGGCUGUUGAAAUGAAGGUUCAGGUUACUGAGCCAGAAGGCCAGGCCAUUGAGCCAGAAGGCCAGCCUAUUAAGACAGAAACUCAGGGUAUUAUGCUGAAAGCCCAGAGUAUUGAGCUAGAAGAAGGGAGUAUUGUGUUGAAAACCCAGGAUUUUCUACCCACAAAUCAGGCUCUUCUAACGAAAAACCAGGAUGUUUUACUCAAAGACCACUGUGUUCUCCCUAAAGACCAGAGUAUUCUACUCAAAUAUCAGGACCAGGACUUCCUACCCAGAGACCAGCAUGUUCUCCACAAAGACCAAGAUAUUCUGCCAAAAUAUCAGGACCAGAAUUUUCUACCUAAGGACCAGAAUUUUUUAUCUAGAGACCAGCAUGUUCUCCCCAAAGACCAAGAUAUUCUGCCAAAAUAUCAGGACCAGAAUUUUCUACCUAAGGACCAGAAUUUUUUGUCUAGAGACCAGCAUGUUCUCCCCAAAGACCAGAAUAUUCUACCUAAAUAUCAAGGCCAGGAUUUUCUACCUAAAGACCAGGACUUUUUAUCUAGAGACCAGCAUGUUCUCCCCAAAGACUGGAAUAUUCUACCCAAAUGUCAGGACCAGGAUUUUCUACCCAGAGACCAAGGUGUUCUUCCCAAAGACCAAAAUAUUCUACCCAUAUGUCAGGACCAGGAUUUUCUACCCAGAGACCAAGGUUAUCUUCCUAAAGACCAAAAUAUUCUACCCAUAUGUCAGGACCGGGAUUUUCUACCCAGAGACCUGCAUGUUCUCUCCAACGACCAGAAUAUUCUACCCAAAUGUCAGGACCAAGAUUUUCUACCAAAAUAUCAGAAAGUACACUUUAAGGAGCCAUACUCUGAUAUGACAGAUGAGAAAGGGAGAGAAGACUUUUCUCUGGCAGACUAUCAGUGUUUGCCUCCCAAAUCCCAGGACCAGGAUGACAUCAAAAAUCAGCAACCUGCAUCUUUUAUGAGAGAAGAAAGAGUGAGAGAAGAAUUGCCUCUGGACUAUCAUCAAUAUGUUGUACCUAAAAUCCAGGACCAAGACUCCCCUAGAGAACAGAACAAGCAUAUCAAACUACCCUCAUCUUUUGAGAAAUGGGAGAUUGCAAGAGGAAAUACUCCUGGAGUGCCCUUGGCUUAUGAUAGGUAUCAAUCAGGAUUGAGCACUGAAUUCCAAGCUCCACUGGCAUUUCAGUCUGACGUGGAUAAAGAAGAAGAUAAGAAAGAGCGUCAAAAGCAGUACCUGAGACAUAGACGACUUUUCAUGGAUAUUGAGAGAGAACAAGUUAAAGAACAACAAAGGCAAAAAGAACAAAAGAAGAAAAUUGAAAAGUAAGUUAUUCGAUCUGCUCUGUGAGCCUUAAAUUGCCAAUUAAGAUGUUUUUGGAAGAUGAACUUUAGAAAAAGGUAAUGGUUUUGCCCUCUGAUCCAUAUUGAAAACAGCUAUUUUUGAUCUGGGUGAAGUAUUGGAAGAUGGUGAACAGCUAUGGUUUGGUUUUUUGGUUCGAUUUUCUAUUAGACUUGAUUUUUUUAGGGCAAUUUUAGGCUCACAGCAAAAUUGAGCAGAAAGUACAGAGAGUAUACCCUCUGCCCCACAAAUGCGUAGCCUCUCCUACUGUCACUAUCCUGCACCAUAGUGGUACAAUGUAUUAGAAUUGAUGAACCUACAUUGACACAUUAUUAUUACCCAAAGUCCAUAGUUUACAUUAGGGUUCACCUUUGGUGUUAGGCAUUCUAUGGGUUUUGACAAAUACAUAAUGUCAUGUGUCUACCAUUAUGGUAUUAUACAAAGUGCUUUCACUUCCCUAAAAUCCUCUGUGCUCUGCCUAUUCCUCCCUCUUUACACCCUAUCCUGUGGUAACCACUGAACUCUCUACUGUCUCCAUGGUUUUGCCUUUUCCAGAACGUCAUAUAGUUGGAAUCAUACAGUAUGUAUGCAACCUUUUUAGAUUGGCUUUUUAUACUUAGAAAUAUGCAUGUACGUUUCCUCUAAUGCUUUUUUAUGGCUUGAUAGCUCAUUUAUUUUUAGCACUGAAUAAUAUCCCAUUAUCUGAAUGUAUCACAGUUUAGUUAUUCAUUCACCUACUGAAGAACAUAUUAUUUGCUGCCAAUAUUUAGCAAUUAUGAAUAAAGCUACUUUAAAAUCUAUGUACAAGUUUUUGUGGGGGCAUACAUUUUUAGCUUAUUUGAGUAAAUAACAAGGCAUAUGAUUGCUGGAUCAUGUGGUAAAAAUAUAUUUAGCUUUAUAAGACACUACCAAAUGGUCUUCCAAAGUGGCUAUACCAUUUUGCAUUCCCACCAGCAAGGAGUGAGGGUUCCUGUUGCUUGACAUCCUUGCCAACAUUUGGUGGUGUCAGUAUUUUGGAUUUUGGCCAUUCUAGUAGGUGUGUAGUAGUAUCUCAUUGUUUUAAUUUUCACUUCCCUAAUGACAUAUAAUAUGGAGCACCUUUUCACAUGCUUAUUUGUCAUCUGUGUAUCUUCUUUGGUGAUGUGUCUGUUCAUUUUGCUUCUUCUUGUUGAAUUUUAAGAGUUCUUUGUAUAUUUUGAAUAACAGUUCUUUAUCAGUCUUUUGUAAACAUUUUUUCCCCAGUCUGUAGCAUGUCUUCUCAUCUGUUGACAGUAUCUUUUGCAGAGCAAAAUGAAGUCUGCCUAAUCAGUUCUUUCUUUCAUGGAUUGUGCCUUUGGUGUUAUAUAUAAAAAAAAGUCACUGCCAUACCCAAAGUCACUUAGAUUUUCUCCUGUGUUACCUUCUAGGAGUUUUGUAGUUUUGCAUUUUACAUUUUUCUCUAUGAUCCACUUUGUUAAUUUUUGUGAGAGGUGUAAGAUCUGUGUUUAGAGUCAUUUUUUUUUUGCAUGUGGAUGUCCAGUUGUUCCAGCACCAUUUGUUGAAAAGACCAUCUUUUAUUAAUCAUAUUGCCUUUGCUCUUUUGUUAAAAAUCAGUUGACUGCAUUUAUGUGGUUCUGUUUUUUGGACUUGGUUCUCUGUUCUGUUCCAUUGAUCUAUUUGUCUAUUCUUUUGCCAUACCACACUGUUUUGAUUAUUGUAGCUUUACUUACAUAUUUUUAUUGAUACAUAAUAAUUGUACAUAUUUAUGGGAUACAUGUAAUAUUUUGAUAACAUGCAAUGUAUAUGAUCAAAUGUAUGAUGUGUAAUGAUCAAAUCAGAGUAAUUUGGAUACCUGUCAUCUCAAACAUUAUGAUUUCUUUGGAUUGGGAACAUUUCAAAUCUUCUAGCUGUUUUGAAAUAUACAAUAAAUUAUUGUUAACUAGAGUCACCCUACUGUGCUACCAAUAAGUAGAAUUUAUUCUAUCUGUCUAACUGUAUGUUUAUACCCAUUAACCCAUUCUUCAUCCUCUCCUCCCUUCCCACCCUCUGGUUAACUAUCAUUCUACUUUCUACCUCUAUGGGAUCAGCUUUUUUAGCUCCCACAUGUGAGUGAGAACAUGCGAUGUUUGUCUUUCUGUGCCUGGCUUAUUUGAUUUAACAUAAUGACUUCCAGUUCCAUCUGUGUUGCAGCAAAUGACAGGAUUUCAUUCUUUUUAUGGCCGAAUAGUAUUCCACUGUGUGUAUAUACCACAUUUUCUUUGUGUCCCUCUGUUGAAGACACUUAGGUUGAUUCAAUAUCUUGACAAUUGUGAAUGGUGCCACAGUAAACAUGGGGAUACAGGUAUACCUUUGAUACACUGAUUUCUUUUCCUUUGAAUAAAUACCCAAUAGUGGAGUUGCUGGAUCAUCUGGAAGUUCUGUUUUUAGGUUUUUUUUUUAGAAAUCUCCAUACCGUUUUCCAUAAUUUCUGUAUUAAUUUACAUUCCCACCAACAGUGUAUAAGAGUUCCCUUUUCUCUACAUCCUCACCAGCUUUUGUUACUUUUUGUUGUUUUGAUAAUUGCCAUUUUAACUGUGGUGAGAUGAUAUCUCAUUGUGGGUAAGUUCAGUUGAUCCCCAGGCACCCGGAUGACAAGCAUGAGUGCCUGAAGUGGCGGCAGUGGGUGAGGCAGGCCUGUCCUCAGGUCGUUUGGUUCUAUACCUGGGUGCUGGCAACAGUGGGUGUGGCAUGUAGCUUUAUAAUAAGUCUUGAAGUCGGGUAAUUUCAGUCUUUCAACUUUGUUUUUCUUUUUUAAUGUUGUGUUGGCUUUACCUCUCUACAUAAACUUUAAAUAAGUUUGUCAAUAUCCACGAAAUAACUUGUUGAGAUUUUUACUGAGAUUGCAGUUAAUGUAUAUAUCAAGUUGGGGAGAACUGACAUCUUGACAAUAUUGAGUCUUUCUAUCCAUGACCAUAGAUGAUCUCUCCAUUUUAUUUAGUUGUCCUUUGAUUUCUUUCUUCAGUGUUUUGUUGUUUUUGCUCAUAUAGAUCUUAUAUAUUUUUUGUUAGACUUAUACCUAAAUCUUUCAUUUUGGAAAUACAUAUAAAUGGUAUUGUGCAUUUAAUUUUAAACUCCACCCGUUCAUUGCUGGUAUAUCGGAAAGUGAUUGACUUUUGUAUAUUAAACUUGUAUCCUUCAACCCUGCUGUAAUCACUUAGUUCCAGUAGCUUGUUCAGUGACAUUUUUGUUAUUAUAUGAUCAUGUCACCAGUGAACAAAGUUAGUUUUAUUUCUUCUUUCCCAGUCUGUAUGCCUUUUAUUUCCUUUCGUUGCCUUAUUUCAUUAGCAAGGACUUUCAGUAUGAUGUUAAUGAGAGGGUACAUCUUUGGCUUGUUUCUUAUCCUAGCAGGUAAACUUACAGUUUCUUACCAUCAAGUAUGAUGUUAGCUGUACAUUUUUUGUAGAUGCGCUUUUUCAGGUUGAAGAAGUUCUUCUCCAUCAGUUGCAUUUCUUUUUCUUUUUUUUUGAUACAGAGUCUCGCUCCGUUGCUAGGCUGGAGUGCAGUGGCGUGAUCUCGGCUCACUGCAACCUCCGCCUCCCUGGUUCAAGAGAUUCUCCUGCCUCAGCCUCUUGAGUAGCUGGGACUACAGGCUAUGGGUUUUUACUGUGCCCCUUAGAGCUCAACCCCAGUUGUCUUGACAAACUUCAUUGUGCCUACUAACUUCUAAACAAUGCAUAAAAAGUUAUAAUGAGCUGGGCGCGGUGGCUCACGCCUGUAAUCCUAGCACUUUGGGAGGCUGAGGCGGGCAGAUCACCUGAGGUCAGGAGUUCGAGACCAGCCUGACCAACGUGGAGUAACCCCGUCUCUACUAAAAAUACAAAACUAGCUGGGCAUGGUGGCUCAUGCUUGUAAUCCUUGUAAUCCCAGCUACUCGGGAGGCUGAGGCAGGGGAAUCACUUGAACACGGGGGGCGGAGGUUGCAGUGAGCCGAGAUCGUGCCAUUGCACUCCAGCCUGGGCAAUAAGAGCGAAACUCCGUCUCAAAAAAAAAAAAAAAGUUAUAAUGAAAUCUAAUAUGAGGAUUUACUUCAUCAGAUGUUAUUGACAUACUAUGCAUAAUGCACUAAACAAAGUGCUAAUAUGUGUAAUAGUUUGAAAUUUGUGAAGUGCUAUAAAAUAUAAAGCAAUAACACUUUUAUUUUGAAACACUCUGUAUAAUACUAUAACAAAAUUGUUAUAGGUUACUGUAAAGUGCUAGAAAUGUGUUCAAAUAGCAUAAUGAAUAGUCUUUGGGGUCUUUUUGGUUUUGUUUUUUAUAAUUUCAACUUCUAUUUUAGAUUCAGGGGGUACAGGUGCAAGUUUGUUACAAGGGUAUAUUGCGUGAUGCUGAAGGUUGUGGUAUAAAUGAUCCUGUCACUCAGAUAGUAAGUAUAGUACCCAAUAGGUAAUUUUCAGCCUUUUCUCCUCCCCUAUCCCUCCCUCUAGUAGUCUUCAGUGUUUAUUGUUUUCAUUUUUGUGUCUACGUGUACCUAAAGUUUAGCUCCCACUUAUAAGUGAGAGCAUGCAGUAUUUGGUUUUCUGUUUCUGUGUUAAUUCGCUUAGGAUAAUGGCUUCCAGCUACAUCCAUGUUGCUGUAAAGGACAUGAUUUCAUUCUUUUAUAUGGUUGCAUAGUCUUCUAUGGUGUAUACAUACCACAUUUUCUUUAUCCAGUUCGCCACUGAUGGGCACCUAGGUUGAUUCUGUGUCUUUGCUGUUUUGAAUAGUGGUGCGAUGAACAUAUGAAUGCGUGUGCCUUUUUGGUAGAAGGAUUCGUUGUACCAAAUUAUGGGAUUGCUAGGUCAAAUGGUAGUUCUAAGUUCUUUGAAAAAUCUCCAAACCGCUUUCCACAGUGGCUGAACUAACAAACCGCUUUCCACAGUGGCUGAACUAAUUUACAUUUCCACCAACAAUGAAUAAGCAUUCCCUUUUCUCUGCAGCCUUGCAAUUAUUUGUUAUUUUUUGACUUUUUACUAAUAUCUGUUUUGACUCGUGUUAGAUAGUAUCUCAUUGUGGUUUUGAUUUGCAUUUCUCUGAUGAUUAGUGAUGUGGAACAUAUUUUCAUGUUUAUUGGCCACUUGUAUGUCUUCUUUUGAGAAGUAUUUAUUCAUGUCUUUUGCCCACUUUUUAAUGGGGUUGUUUUUUGCUUUGCCUGGUGUUUUUUUUUUUUUUUAAGAUGGAGUCUCACUCUGUCCAGUGGCACAUUCUCAGCUCACUGCAAUGUCUGCCUCCCAGAUUCAAGUGAUUCUCGUGCCUAUCUCCUGAGUAGCUGGGACUACAGGCAUGUACCACCAUGCCCAGCUAAUUUUUGUAUUUUUAGUAGAGACAGGGUUUCACCAUGUGGGCCAGGCUGGUCUCGAACUCCUGACCUCAGGUGAUCCACUUGCCUUGGCCUCCUAAUUUGGGGGAAUUACAGGAGUGAGCUACCACGCCUGGCCAAAUUGUUUAAAUUCCUUAUAGAUACUGGAUAUCAGACCUUUGUCAGGUGCAUAGUUUGUAAAUAUCUUCUACCAUUCUGUAGGUUGUCUGUUUAUGCACUUGAUAGUUUCUCUUGCUGUGAGGAAGCUCUUUAGUUUGAGUCCCAUUUAUCAAUUUUUGCUUUUGUUGCAAUUGCUUUUGAGGAUUUAGUCAUAAAUUUUUUGCCAAAGCUGAUGUCCAGAGUGGUACUUCCUGGGUUUUCUUCUAGGAUUUUCAUAGUUUGAGGUCUUACAUUUAAAUCUUUAAUCCAUCUUGAGUUAAUGUUUGUGUAUAGUAAAGGUAGGGGUCCAGUUUCAUUCUUCUGCAUUUGCCUAACCAGUUAUCCCAGCACCAUUUAUUGAAUAAGGAGUCCUUUCCCUAAUGGGUAGUCAUUGGACCUAAAAGUUUCCUAGUUCCUUUUCAAUGCUAUUUCAUCUUAAUGAAAAAAAAAUAAACCUUUUAAUUAGUAAUCCAUUUCUUCUCUUGUAUUACUAACAAGUUUUCCUUCAUCUUAAUGGGCAACUGUUUCUGUAAUAGAAGUAUUAUUAUUAUUAUUAUUAUUAUUAUUAUUUUUUAAGAUGGAGUUUCACUCUUGUCGCCCAGGCUGGAGUGCAAUGGCACGAUCUCGACUCACUGCAACCUCCACCUCCCGAGUUCAAGCGAUUCUCCUGCCUCAGCUUCCCAAGUAGCUGGGACCACAGGCGUAUGCCACCAAGCCCGGCUAAUUUUUGUAUUUUUAGUAGAGACAGGGUUUCACCAUCUUGGCCAGGCUGAUCUCGAACUCCUGACCUCGUGAUCCACCCGCCUCAGCCUCCCAAUGUGCUGGGAUUACAGGGUUGAGCCACCAUGCCCGGCCGAAGUAUUCUUUAUUUAGAAGAAUUCAUUUAAAAAAACAAUGACUGCUGGUGUAGUAGCCAUGUCAAAGGCAAUAUUUAUUGGAUUAUUUUAAGUGCUUUCACAUGUAUUUUCAUUUAUUUGUAGUUUAUUCGUGGGAUAACUGAUUUAAGCCUGCCUCUAAUAUUUGCAGGAUUGGGCUCACAUACAAAUACAAGUUUAUGUACCUUACAUCUAAGUAUUUUAAUGUCAUAAGCUGAGCUAAAAAACUGUAAAAUGACAUAUAUUCUAUUGUCCUACCUUGACAAAUAUGAUUUCAUAGUGACUAGAAGGUCGGACUCAAAUUUGCAAUUCUUGAACUCCUCUGAGUUACAUGCAGGAACAUGAGUGGAGAGUCAGCCUCCAGUCCACCCCCUUUCUAUUCUUAUUCAUACCUCUAUUUUGUACUGGAAGAAUUUCAGAUACAUGCUAUGGUUCAACUCAGCCCAGAUAUCUAAGUUCUAGGUACAUGCCCUGUAAGUGGUCACCCCUUAAUGUUCCAUUGAGCCUAGAUGCGCAUGAGAGGUGCAGCCUGCUCUGAGGAAGACAAAGGUGGGGAACAGAACUGUGUAUACCCUAAAAACAGCCUUGGAAAGUUUGAGUAAAGAAUUCCAGGGGCCUGGGUACCUGGAGCAGAGUAUAGAUGGGCAGUCAUAGGCUUCAGGUGCCUUCGCCUAGUUGCUUAGUCUCUGAGGACUAUGGGAAGAGAUAUGGUCAGAGACAGGCCAAAGUGGGACUAUUAAAAAUGUGGGUCUCAUGAUAAGGGCUCCCCUCUUAUCCAGGUCUAAGAGUGAUUCUGCAUUUAUUCAGAAAACAUUUAUUUUUUAUCUUCCAUAUCAUAGGCACUGUCCUAGGCUCAGAUGAUACAAAGAUAAAUAAAAUUCAUUCCUUUUCUUGAAGAACUCAUAAUCUAAGUUGGGGAGGGAGGAUGAGAAACAAACAUAUUCAAAUAAGUAAUAUAAUUAGUGCAGUUGCCAAGAUAGGUACAGAGUCCAUGUGAGCACAGAAGAAGGGAUUAACGAUUUUAUCUGGAGAGUUAGAGAAAAUAUUACACUUUAGUUGGGUUUGGGUGGAUAAAUAUAUGUUUUGCAGGGAAGGGGAUAAGGAUGGUGAGUUAGGAAAACAUAUAUAAACAGAAUCAAGGUGGGAGGAAAUAAUAGUAGUAUUCAUGCAGAAUUUUUAUAAUUCACAAGGGCUUUCAUAUAUUAUCUAGUUUAGUACUUUUCAACAACAAAGCAAACAUUUAUUGAAAACUUACUACAUGCCAGGGACUGUUCUAUAUGCUGAGAAUAUAAAACUAGAAUAUAUGACAGGAUAGUACAUAUUUACAAAUGGACUUAAGUGUGAAUGUAUCCCUUAUGAACUUUGUAAACUUAAGCAAGUAACUUCACCUCUGAGCCUCAGUAUCCUUAAUUAUAUAAUGGAGAUUAUAAUAUUGAUCUUCUAGUUUGUUGAUAGCAUUAAGUGGAGAAAUGUAUGUAAAGUACUUAACAUUGUAUCUGACAUUUAAUAAGAUCUCAAUAAAAAGUACCUGUUACUACCAUGAUAGGAUGAGCACCAAGAGAGGACAGACAACAGGAGAAAAAGAGACAAAAAAUAAUUAUAAUGCUUAAAGUGAGGCAGGGAUAGUCUAGGGAGGUCAAGAAAUGCUUUAUAGAUGAGUUAAUACUCAAGCUACAUCUUAAAGGAUGAAUUGAAGUUUGCCAGAUGGUCAAGGAGCUUAGUAUGAAGCAUAAGGUGUGUCUGAGAAAUAAAAUAAAAAUUUGGGGUGGCUAAACCCCAAGUGAAGUGAAGUGGCAGAGAAUCUAUAACGAAGUUGUUGAAAGAUUUUAAGGCAAAAGUCCUAUAAUCUUACUAUAAUCUUAUAAAGACCAGUCUGGCAGCUGCAUAUAGAAUAAUCUAAAAAAGAAAACUAAGGCAGAGUCCAGUUAAGAAGUUAUUAUAGUAGUUGUGGAGGACGAUGAGGGCACUGGGAACAGAGAGUGACAUAUUUAAUAAUAUUUAAGAAGUAGAAUCCAUAGAUUUUGAUGACCAAAUUCUUAGUCUUGAUGGGUUUGGUCAAGGGUAUUUUCUAACUUUCUUCUUAGAUAAUUGAAUGAAUGGUUAGUACCAUUAACGUAUAUAGGGAAUGUUCAAAGAACAGAUUUUUCAGGAAGCUAGUGAGUUCAGUUUGUGACCAUCAGCUUCAGGAGCAUGUGAAAUAUUAAGGGAGGUCUGAUUUAUAUGCAUGUGAAAAUAACUAAAGUUCUGGGAACAAUAGGAACUAAGUAUUUCUUAAGGGGUUUUCAAAAUAUGUUUCAGCAUGACAUUGGAUAAGGUACAGGGCUACUGCUGGGUGACAGAAACAAGCAGAGCUUUUGGUGGUCUGAAGGAGCUGCAGUAACAAAAUUGGAGACUCAAGGGUCUCAAACAUUUGAUCAGUGUUCUCCUCAAGACAUUUGCCAAAGUCUAAGAAAACAUGAAGGCUAAAUGGAAAAUGAGUGGAAAAGAGACUAAGAAUCUAUUAGUCUGUGAUGAUGAGGAGAUGUAGAGUUCAGGACCCACUGGGUUGGGGGAGGGGAGAAAGGGCCCAAUAUACAUAUCAGGCUUUCAGUUGAGUUAGGGAGAGCAUACACUAAGAACAUCGUCUAACUAGCAGUAGAAUAAACCUUACCUAAAUUACAAAGCAGCCUUGAUUCUGCUGAUGUCUGGACCAGAUUAAGAUGAUGAACUGUGUACUUUCUGCCUAGCUGAGAAAAGUGUGAACUUUCUCUGGUUAUGGAUAACAUAAUUUAGAGCCUCUAAAAAAUUAAAACAAUAUUCAGUAUUCAAUCAAAAGUUUCUAAGUACAUACUUAGAAGUAGAUGUCCAAAAGCCAAGAGAAAGAAAAGACAACAGAAGCAGACUCAGAUGACACAAGAUACUAGUAUUAGUAGACUUUAAAAUAAUUGAUUAAUGUGCUCAGGUAACUAGAGGAAGAGAUGGAGAAAAUGGAUGAAAAUAUUGAGAAUUUCACCAAAGAAAUGGAAUCUAUAAAAUAGAAUCCAAUAGAAAAAUAUAAUCUUAAAAUAAGAACUCACUCUAUGCACAAUGAGGUACCACUUCAGACUCACUAGAGUAGCUUAAGGAGGGAAAGACAACAAACUUAACAGUACCAGAUAGUGGCAAGGAUGUAGAACAGCUGUAACUCAUGUAUUAGUAUCAUAUGUAGAAAACAGCACAACCACUUUGGAAAACUGUUUAAUAUCUUAUACAGUUAAACAUAGACCUACUAUAUGACCCAACCAAUUUAUGCCUAGAAAUUUAAGAAAAGUGGAAACAUUUAUAAAAACACUGAAUCGUGACAGAAUAUAUUCCUUUCAAGUGCCCGUGGAACAUUUUCCACAGUUCAUCUUACUUUUGGUUAUUUUUCAGAAUAUGUUCUGUAACUUUAGUGAUAUUACACUAGAAAUCAAUAAGCAGUAUAUUUCUAAAGGAUCAUGGAUCACAGAAAAAAUUAUAAUGGCAAUUAGGAAAUACUUUUGAGAGAAUAAUAAUGAAGAUAAAUCAUAUUAAAACUUUUUAGGUGUCACUGAAGCAGUCCUUAAAGGGAAUGUCAGAGCCUUGAUUACAAUUAAUAUAAAAUUAAAAAGGCUACAAAUCAAUGUUUUAACCUUCCAUCUUAAGCUUGGGAAAAACUACAAAUUACAUCAGAAAAAAAGCCAUAGGAAUAAGUGCAAAAUCGGUGAAAUAUAAAACAAAUGUAUAACAGAGGAAAUCAAAGACAAAAGUUGGUUCUUUUAAAAAUUUUGUUUUGCCAAGGAUAUAUCACUUUUACUAAUCAGUAAAAAGAAAAAACACAAUUCACCAAUAUUAGGAAUGGAAAGGGAACCAUUACUACAGAGCCUACAGACAUUAAAUCACAGUAAGAGAACAUUAUAAACAACUUUACAUUUUAAAAAUUUGACAAUUUUAAUAAAAUAAACUCCUAUGGGGAUAAAACAACUAAAAUGGACACAAGAAGAAAUUGAAUACUUGAGUAAUCCCGUAUCACUGAAAGAAAUAAAACCAGUUAUUAAAAAUCCUGAAAGAAAAAUCCAGGUUCAGAUUCCAGCUCAUAUAUCUUCACUGGGGAAUUCUUUUUAAAUGUAUAAGGGAAAAAAUAACAUAAAGUUUUACAUAAAUUCUUCCAGAGAAUGGAAAGUGGAAUAUUUCUCAAAUAAAGCAUAACUUUAAUACCAGCCUGAUGGGGACAUUACAAGAAAGCAGCAUUACAGACUAAUUUUUCUUGUGAGCAUAAAUGAAAAAAGCCUCAAGUGAAAUAUUGGCACAAUGAUCUUUGAGGGGCACUGCUGCAGGCCCCUAUACUUGCAGCUUCUGCUUAAGCCCCUGCCUCUAGCCCCCGGGCAGCUUCUUAACCACCCCUGAACUUCUCCCAAGCUAUGGACCAAAUGGAAACAAAGCUUUUUGCAGCAACAGCAAUCAUACAAUGAAUAACAUACUGAAAUAAAAUAUUCCAAGAUGUUAAA